AUUCCCAGCCUCACAUCACUCACACCUUGCAUUUCACCCCUGCAUCCCAGUCGCCCUGCAGCCUCACACAGAUCCUGCACACACCCAGACAGCUGGCGCUCACACAUUCACCGUUGGCCUGCCUCUGUUCACCCUCCAUGGCCCUGCUACUGGCCCUCAGCCUGCUGGUUCUCUGGACUUCCCCAGCCCCAACUCUGAGUGGCACCAAUGAUGCUGAAGACUGCUGCCUGUCUGUGACCCAGAAACCCAUCCCUGGGUACAUCGUGAGGAACUUCCACUACCUUCUCAUCAAGGAUGGCUGCAGGGUGCCUGCUGUAGUGUUCACCACACUGAGGGGCCGCCAGCUCUGUGCACCCCCAGACCAGCCCUGGGUAGAACGCAUCAUCCAGAGACUGCAGAGGACCUCAGCCAAGAUGAAGCGCCGCAGCAGUUAACCUAUGACCGUGCAGAGGGAGCCCGGAGUCCGAGUCAAGCAUUGUGAAUUAUUACCUAACCUGGGGAACCGAGGACCAGAAGGAAGGACCAGGCUUCCAGCUCCUCUGCACCAGACCUGACCAGCCAGGACAGGGCCUGGGGUGUGUGUGAGUGUGAGUGUGAGCGAGAGGGUGAGUGUGGUCAGAGUAAAGCUGCUCCACCCCCAGAUUGCAAUGCUACCAAUAAAGCCGCCUGGUGUUUACAACUAA